AAAAGGGGCUGAAAUCCUGGGGACCUCAGAGUCGUCUAAAACUCCUAGCCAUGUUCCAGCAGUUCCAGGCCUCCUGUCUUGUCCUGUUUUUCCUGGUUGGCUUUGCUCAGCAGACCCUAAAGCCUCAAAAUAGGAAGGUGGAUUGCAACAAAGGGGUAACAGGCACCAUCUAUGAGUAUGGAGCCCUCACCCUCAACGGCGAGGAGUACAUCCAAUUCAAGCAGUUUGCAGGCAAGCACGUCCUGUUUGUCAAUGUGGCCGCCUAUUGAGGCUUGGCAGCUCAGUAUCCUG